AGUUCCCACUGCAGCGCAGGUGAGCUCUCCUGAGGACCUCUCUGUCAGCUCCCCUGAUUGUAGGGAGGAUCCAGUGUGGCAAGAAACUCCUCCAGCCCAGCAAGCAGCUCAGGAUGUUCCUGAAGGCCGUGGUCCUGACCCUGGCCCUGGUGGCUGUCGCCGGAGCCAGGGCUGAGGUCAGUGCUGACCAGGUGGCCACGGUGAUGUGGGACUACUUCAGCCAGCUGAGCAACAAUGCCAAGGAGGCCGUGGAACAUCUCCAGAAAUCUGAACUCACCCAGCAACUCAAUGCCCUCUUCCAGGACAAACUUGGAGAAGUGAACACUUACGCAGGUGACCUGCAGAAGAAGCUGGUGCCCUUUGCCACCGAGCUGCAUGAACGCCUGGCCAAGGACUCGGAGAAACUGAAGGAGGAGAUUGGGAAGGAGCUGGAGGAGCUGAGGGCCCGGCUGCUGCCCCAUGCCAAUGAGGUGAGCCAGAAGAUCGGGGACAACCUGCGAGAGCUUCAGCAGCGCCUGGAGCCCUACGCGGACCAGCUGCGCACCCAGGUCAGCACGCAGGCCGAGCAGCUGCGGCGCCAGCUGACCCCCUACGCACAGCGCAUGGAGAGAGUGCUGCGGGAGAACGCCGACAGCCUGCAGGCCUCGCUGAGGCCCCACGCCGACGAGCUCAAGGCCAAGAUCGACCAGAACGUGGAGGAGCUCAAGGGACGCCUUACGCCCUACGCUGACGAAUUCAAAGUCAAGAUUGACCAGACCGUGGAGGAGCUGCGCCGCAGCCUGGCUCCCUAUGCUCAGGACACGCAGGAGAAGCUCAACCACCAGCUUGAGGGCCUGACCUUCCAGAUGAAGAAGAACGCCGAGGAGCUCAAGGCCAGGAUCUCGGCCAGUGCCGAGGAGCUGCGGCAGAGGCUGGCGCCCUUGGCCGAGGACGUGCGUGGCAACCUGAGGGGCAACACCGAGGGGCUGCAGAAGUCACUGGCAGAGCUGGGUGGGCACCUGGACCAGCAGGUGGAGGAGUUCCGACGCCGGGUGGAGCCCUACGGGGAAAACUUCAACAAAGCCCUGGUGCAGCAGAUGGAACAGCUCAGGCAGAAACUGGGCCCCCAUGCGGGGGACGUGGAAGGCCACUUGAGCUUCCUGGAGAAGGACCUGAGGGACAAGGUCAACUCCUUCUUCAGCACCUUCAAGGAGAAAGAGAGCCAGGACAAGACUCUCUCCCUCCCUGAGCUGGAGCAACAGCAGGAACAGCAGCAGGAGCAGCAGCAGGAGCAGGUGCAGAUGCUGGCCCCUUUGGAGAGCUGAGCUGCCCCUGGUGCACUGGCCCCACCCUCGUGGACACCUGCCCUGCCCUGCCACCUGUCUGUCUGUCUGUCCCAAAGAAGUUCUGGUAUGAACUUGAGGACACAUGUCCAGUGGGAGGUGAGACCACCUCUCAAUAUUCAAUAAAGCUGCUGAGAAUCUAGCCUCAA